GCGGCAGGCCGGCGGGCAGGCUCGGCGUGUCCCUUCCGUCCGGCCCGCGCCGGCGGCGGGGAGGCGGCGCGCGGCCCGCAGCCCGCCCAUGGAGGCUUUCCCCUGGGCGCCCCGCUCGCCCCGCCGCGGCCGCGCCCCCCCGCCCAUGGCGCUCGUGCCCAGCGCCCGCUACGUGAGCGCCCCGGGCCCGGCGCACCCGCAGCCCUUCAGCUCCUGGAACGACUACCUGGGGCUCGCCACGCUCAUCACCAAAGCGGUGGACGGCGAGCCGCGCUUCGGCUGCGCCCGCGGUGGGAACGGCGGCGGCGGCUCCCCGCCCUCCUCCUCCUCGUCGUCCUGCUGCUCCCCCCACACGGGGGCCGGGCCUGGGGCGCUGGGGCCGGCGCUGGGGCCGCCCGACUACGACGAGGACGACGACGACGACAGCGACGAGCCGGGGUCCCGGGGCCGCUACCUGGGGAGCGCGCUGGAAUUGCGCGCGCUGGAGCUGUGCGCGGGCCCCGCCGAGGCCGGGCUGCUGGAGGAGCGCUUCGCCGAGCUGAGCCCGUUCGCGGGUCGUGCCGCCGCCGUGCUGCUGGGCUGCGCGCCCGCCGCCGCCGCCGCCGCCACCACCACCAGCGAGGCGACGCCGCGCGAGGAGCGGGCCCCGGCGUGGGCGGCCGAGCCCCGGCUGCACGCGGCCUCCGGGGCGGCGGCCGCCCGGCUGCUGAAGCCCGAGCUGCAGGUGUGCGUGUUCUGCCGGAACAACAAGGAGGCGAUGGCGCUCUACACCACCCAUAUCCUCAAGGGCCCCGACGGGCGAGUGCUGUGUCCCGUGCUGCGCCGCUACACGUGUCCCCUGUGCGGCGCCAGCGGCGACAACGCGCACACCAUCAAGUACUGCCCGCUCUCCAAAGUGCCGCCGCCGCCCGCCCGCCCGCCGCCCCGCAGCGCCAGGGACGGCCCGCCUGGCAAGAAGCUGCGCUGAAGGCCCGGGCUCCCGGCCGCCCAGGGUCGCCGCCGCCCCUCGCACCGCUAGGUCUGCGCACCAUCUCGCCCCCGCCGUGGGGAGGCGUGCGGCUCAGCGGUCGGCUCGACAUGGGACGUCGUCCUGGUGGUUUUUGAAAAGCAGCCGACCGUGUGGAGUACUUCCGUGCUGAACGAUUGGGACUAGACGCUGAAAUCCCCAUUUGUCUUCAGUUUCUAGUUUGCACAUCCAGAACGGCGAAGGCUGGGUGUGUAUUCCACUAACUGAAAUAUGGCAACUUAGAGGCGCUGUUUAUUUACUGUAUACGUCGACCUAUUUUAGAUGCGCAUCAGUAUGAAAUUGUCUCAAUCUUGGAUGUUUCAUUUUAUGAAUGGAGGCACUUUACUAGGUCUAGAAUAUUUUUUUAAAAGCCUCUGAACUGAGCUUAAAACUGGCGAUUUUAUGAAAUGUCGGCAAAAUGACUAUUUUAUUGUUUGAAGCGAGUUAAUAUUCUCAGUUGUCUUUAAAAAUCAGUUACUCUAAUUCCAGGUGAAGCAAGCCGCUGGUAGCAUCACCCUUAUGAGAAGUGAAGGUUUUGUAAACUUUCCAGUAUUAAUUUGGGCGGGUAUUCCCCGCUUGUGGCUUGUUUCUGUCCUAGCUGGAGGUGUAAAAUGCACAAUGUGUAGCAGGUAGAAUACAGCUCCUUAUCGUUCUAUGUACCAGGUAUUUUAUUACUGAACUAGCAACUAGCCUUUUCCACCUUUAAAAGUUGUGCCAAGUCAUAAUCAUAUUGUGUAUAACUUGGAAAUGGUGCUGUUUAAAAAAAUUGUGUAUUUAUACAGUAACAGUAUGAAUUCAUUAAUCUCACCUGUAACUUUCCUACUUGGCAUUUUCUCUACACACUCACCCUCUUCCAGUUCUUUAAAAACGUUUAUGAUAUUAAGAUCAAAGGGAGGAAGGGAAGACAGCAGUAUUAAUUCACCCUAGAUUACUCAAUUUCAGGGUUCCUAGUGGAGGAAAGCCCAUUCCAGCUGUUGCCUGUCAAACAAAUAGAAGAUGGAUCUCUAGCUCUGAGCUAUUCGUGUAUUAACUCGUAUUCAAGAAGGUUCCACCGUGGGCUGCGUCUGACUUUAAUACAGGCAGUGCUCAAACUAGAAUAAGCACUAAUUAAAGGAAUUGUUGGGGGUCCUUCAUGUGUUCCCACUCCUACUGGAAGACCCAUGUCGGUUUCCGGAACCCCACCAGUUUACCCAUAAGCAAGACUAAACCUGAUCCUUGGGCAAAAGUUCCUAACCCCUACUUUACCCUCCCACCCUCACUUUUAAAUCCACCAUACUGAAUGCCACACUAUGGAAUGCAGCUACCUGCCAAGCAAGGCAAUAGAAGGCAAAAAAUGGAAGUGAAUUAAGAUGAACUCAUCUGAAAUACACAAAUGCAUUACUAUCUGAAGAUACCAGCAAGAGUUUAGUCUACGUGUAUAAGGCUCCCAGUAGGAUUUAGCUAGGCUACUAGAAGUUAGACUGCUUUCGCAUUAAACAGCUAACUUCAUCCACAGCAAAUUGACUCAAUCAGGAACCUUCAUUUGAAGGUGUGUUAGAGGAUGGGGUAAAUACCCGAUAGCUGUCUUUUUGGUGAAAGAAAAGGUGCAUUUCAAGAACUUGGGGGGCAGGAGGAAAGCACAAUGUUUCUUAGCCAGGAAAGACAAAUAAUCCAACGCUGCUAGUCUUAACCCCAGACCAGAGAGAACUGCAGAUCUGACUGGGCCUAAAUUAAGUAGCUUAAUGAAACCAUGUAAUUACUUGUUCUCCUUUCUUUUGCUAUAGAAAAUCUACCAGUUUAAAUGAGCUUCACCUUCUGGGUGAAGUUUCUAAGGUCAACAUGAAUCCUCUUACCUCUCUCACUGCUCGUGUUCUGCCUUUUCAAAAGGACCACUAUGAACAGAUCAGCGCAUUCUCUAGGCCAAAAGGGCUAGCCAGGUGGCAAGAUCAAUUUAGCUACUUUGUAUUUUCAGAGUCAAAUUACAGACGGUUUCCAAAGGUCUUGAGCAUGGGGCUUUGGCAUAGCCUCAAUAUAUGGGAGUCACUGUGAUGAGAUGUGCCUAAUGUUAAUUUGAUAUUCUGACAUUGCUAUUUUACCAGAACUAAGAACAUAUUGAGCUGGAGCUUCUUGAGGGCAGGAGAGUAUUGGAAAAGGAAUCCAGAAGACCCUCUCCACUACUCAGGCAGCCACUAUUCAUCUAUUUUUAAAGUACCCCAUUUUCAGGCCGGGUGUGGUGGCUCAUGCCUGUAAUCCCAGCACUUUGGGAGGCGAGGCGGGGGUGGAUCACAAGGUCAGGAGACCAGCCUGGCCAACAUGGCGAAGCCCCGUCUCUACUAAAAAUACAAAAAUUAGCCGGGUGGUGUGGUGGGCGCCUGUAAUCCCAGCUCCUCAGGAGGCUGAGGCAGGAGAAUUGCUUGAAACCAGGAGGCGGAGGUUGCAGUGAGCCCAGAUCACGCCACUGCACUCCAGCCUGAGCAACAGAGCGACUCUGUCUCCAAAAAAGAAAAAAAGUACCCCAUGUUCAGCCCCUGUGCCAAAUUUGCCUAGGUUUUCCAGCUGACAAUGAAUACUGGGAGUUAAAACGCAGAGUAUUACUAUAGUUAAUUUUCUAGGGUUCUCUUAUGAAAAGUAUAUGUAAACACAUUCAUUUAAAAAUCCUUGGAACUCAAUGUGGAACUUUAAACAUUUUGCAAAAUUACAUUUAGAGAAACCCAAUUUUUCAAAGUUUAAGAAAUAUACAAAGUAUGACAAAAUUAUCUUCAUAAGAACAUGCUGCAUACUUGCCUAGUAGCAAAACAAUACAGGGAAGAGUCAAAAGGGCUUCUCCAACUGUAGAGGUACAGAUUGUCUUAACCUGUUCUUUUCUGUACAGACUUAAAAUUUCUAGUGGCUUUUAUUUUUCUUUGUAUUUUAAUUUUCCUACAAAGUCCUUUUUGGAAGUUGCAGAAUUAUUAGCUUUGAUGAGAACAACUUUUGUCAUAGAUUUGAUUUAUUAAACCAAAAUUAUACAUAUUAAAAUUAUAUCACAAAUA